AGGCGACUGGUUGUUACCGAGGAAGAUGGCGGCGCCAGACCCGAGGCGCUAGGGAAGAUCGCACCGCGGACGCCCGCUGAGCUUGGCGCACGGGCCGACCAGGAGCUGGUGACUGCCCUCAUGUGUGAUUUGCGGCGGCCAGCGGCAGGUGGGAUGAUGGACUUGGCCUACGUCUGUGAGUGGGAGAAAUGGUCCAAGAGCACCCACUGCCCAUCGGUGCCCCUGGCCUGCGCCUGGUCCUGCCGAAAUCUCAUCGCCUUCACCAUGGACCUGCGCAGCGAUGACCAGGACCUGACCCGCAUGAUCCACAUCCUGGACACGGAGCACCCCUGGGACCUGCACUCGAUCCCCUCAGAGCACCACGAGGCCAUCACCUGCCUGGAGUGGGACCAGUCAGGCUCCCGGCUCCUGUCAGCAGAUGCCGACGGGCAGAUCAAGUGCUGGAGCAUGGCGGACCACCUGGCUAAUAGCUGGGAGAGCUCAGUGGGCAGCCUAGUGGAGGGGGACCCCAUUGUGGCCCUGUCCUGGCUGCACAAUGGUGUGAAACUGGCCCUGCACGUGGAGAAGUCGGGCGCCUCCAGCUUCGGGGAGAAGUUCUCCCGAGUCAAGUUCUCACCGUCGCUCACGCUGUUCGGCGGCAAGCCCAUGGAGGGCUGGAUCGCGGUGACGGUCAGCGGCCUGGUCACCGUGUCCCUGCUGAAGCCCAGCGGGCAGGUGCUGACGUCCACCGAGAGCCUGUGCCGGCUGCGCGGCCGCGUGGCCCUGGCCGACAUCGCCUUCACCGGCGGCGGCAACAUCGUGGUGGCCACGGCGGACGGCAGCAGCGCGUCGCCCGUGCAGUUCUACAAGGUGUGCGUGAGCGUGGUGAGCGAGAAGUGCCGUAUCGACACGGAGAUCCUGCCCUCCCUGUUCAUGCGCUGCACCACCGACCUCAACCGCAAGGACAAGUUUCCCGCCAUCACCCACCUCAAGUUCCUGGCCCGGGACAUGUCGGAGCAGGUGCUUUUGUGCGCGUCCAGCCAGACCAGCAGCAUCGUGGAGUGCUGGUCCCUGCGCAAGGAGGGACUCCCCGUGAACAACAUCUUCCAGCAGAUCUCCCCCGUGGUUGGCGACAAACAGCCCACAAUUCUCAAAUGGCGGAUCCUAUCGGCCACCAACGAUCUGGACCGUGUGUCGGCCGUGGCGCUGCCCAAGCUGCCCAUCUCGCUCACCAACACCGACCUCAAGGUGGCCAGCGACACACAGUUCUACCCUGGCCUCGGGCUGGCCCUGGCCUUCCACGACGGCAGCGUCCACAUCGUGCACCGGCUCUCACUGCAGACCAUGGCCGUCUUCUACAGCUCCGCGGCCCCGAGGCCUGUGGAUGAGCCGGCCAUGAAGCGCCCCCGCACCGCGGGCCCCGCCGUCCACUUAAAGGCUAUGCAGCUAUCGUGGACGUCACUGGCCCUGGUGGGGAUUGACAGCCACGGGAAGCUGAGCGUGCUCCGCCUCUCACCUUCCAUGGGCCACCCGCUGGAGGUGGGGCUGGCGCUGCGGCACCUGCUCUUCCUGCUGGAGUACUGCAUGGUGACCGGCUACGACUGGUGGGACAUCCUGCUGCACGUGCAGCCCAGUAUGGUACAGAGCCUGGUGGAGAAGCUGCACGAGGAGUACACGCGCCAGACCGCUGCCCUGCAGCAGGUCCUCUCCACCCGGAUCCUGGCCAUGAAGGCCUCGCUCUGCAAGCUGUCGCCCUGCACGGUGACCCGCGUGUGCGACUACCACACCAAGCUCUUCCUCAUCGCCAUCAGCUCCACCCUGAAGUCGCUGCUGCGCCCCCACUUUCUCAACACGCCUGACAAGAGCCCCGGCGACCGGCUGACCGAGAUCUGCACCAAGAUCACCGACGUCGACAUUGACAAGGUCAUGAUCAACCUCAAGACGGAGGAAUUUGUGCUGGACAUGAACACACUGCAGGCGCUGCAGCAGCUCUUGCAGUGGGUGGGCGACUUCGUGCUGUACCUGCUGGCCAGCCUACCCAACCAGGGUUCCCUGCUGAGGCCGGGCCACAGCUUUCUGCGGGACGGCACCUCGCUGGGCAUGCUUCGGGAAUUGAUGGUGGUCAUCCGCAUCUGGGGCCUUCUGAAGCCCAGCUGCCUGCCCGUGUAUACGGCCACCUCGGAUACCCAGGACAGCAUGUCCCUGCUCUUCCGCCUGCUCACCAAGCUCUGGAUCUGCUGUCGCGAUGAGGGCCCAGCGAGCGAGCCGGACGAGGCGCUGGUGGAUGAAUGCUGCCUGCUGCCCAGCCAGCUGCUUAUCCCCAGCCUGGACUGGCUGCCAGCCAGCGACGGCCUGGUUAGCCGCCUGCAGCCCAAGCAGCCCCUUCGUCUGCAGUUUGGCCGGGCGCCCACGCUGCCUGGCAGUGCUGCCACCCUGCAGCUCGACGGCCUCGCCAGGGCCCCAGGCCAGCCCAAGAUCGACCACCUGCGGAGGCUGCACCUUGGCGCUUGCCCCACGGAGGAAUGCAAGGCCUGCACCAGGUGCGGCUGUGUCACCAUGCUCAAGUCGCCCAACAGAACCACGGCGGUGAAGCAGUGGGAGCAGCGCUGGAUCAAGAACUGCCUGGCUGUUGAAGGCCGUGGGCCGGACGCCUGCGUGACCAGCAGAGCUUCUGAGGAAGCCCCUGCCUUUGUCCAGCUGGGCCCGCAGUCCACACACCACUCUCCCAGGACCCCCAGAUCCCUGGACCAUCUGCAUCCAGAGGACCGUCCGUGACGGCCGGGGGUCCAGGCGGACCUUGUGGUGACCCGGCUCGGGCGUCUCCUCGGUUUCCUUGCCUCACCCGCGGAGAGCGCUGAACCUGGACAAGCAGCGGCUGGGAAGGACAGGUCCAAUAAACGCCCUCUGCGCCCA